AUGAGUGGGGAGAAUGUCACCAAGGUCAGCACCUUCAUCCUGGUGGGCCUCCCCACGGCCCCAGGGCUGCAGUACCUGCUCUUCCUCCUCUUCCUGCUCACCUACCUCUUUGUCCUGGUGGAGAACCUGGCCAUCAUCCUCAUCGUCUGGAGCAGCACCUCCCUCCACAGGCCCAUGUACUACUUUCUGAGCUCCAUGUCUUUCCUGGAGAUCUGGUACGUGUCUGACAUCACCCCCAAGAUGCUGGAGGGCUUCCUCCUCCAGCAGAAACGCAUCUCUUUCGUCGGGUGCAUGACGCAGCUCUACUUCUUCAGCUCCCUGGUGUGCACCGAGUGUGUGCUUCUGGCCUCCAUGGCCUACGACCGCUACGUGGCCAUCUGCCACCCGCUGCGCUACCACGUCCUUGUGACCCCGGGGCUGUGCCUCCAGCUGGUGGGCUUCUCCUUUGUGAGUGGCUUCACCAUCUCCAUGAUCAAGGUCUGUUUUAUCUCCAGCGUCACGUUCUGUGGCUCCAACGUCUUGAACCACUUCUUCUGUGACAUUUCCCCCAUCCUCAAGCUGGCCUGCACGGACUUCUCCACUGCAGAGCUGGUGGAUUUCAUCCUGGCCUUCAUCAUCCUGGUGUUUCCGCUCCUGGCCACCAUACUGUCAUAUUGGCACAUCACCCUGGCUGUCCUGCGCAUCCCCUCGGCCACCGGCUGCUGGAGAGCCUUCUCUACCUGCGCCUCUCACCUCACCGUGGUCACCGUCUUCUAUACAGCCUUGCUUUUCAUGUAUGUCCGGCCCCAAGCCAUUGAUUCCCAGAGCUCCAACAAGCUCAUCUCUGCCGUGUACACUGUUGUCACGCCAAUAAUUAACCCUUUGAUUUACUGCCUGAGGAACAAGGAAUUUAAGGACGCCUUGAAAAAGGCCUUGGGCUUGGGUCAAACUUCACACUAA